CUUUCUACCCUCAAUGCCGAGCACAGAACCUGGGGCAGUGUUUCCACUGUGCUUCCAGUCCCGAGCAUUUCGGAUGAAUGAAUGAUGAACAAACGACAGAACGCAGGGCGAGCAGCUCAGCAAAGGUCAUGCAGGAGAUAGAGAAGCGCUGUGUCAUGAGUAUUGGAUCAUUAUGGAUUUUUUUCUUUCUCAUUGUGCAGAUCUAUUCGCACAACUCUAUCUUCAACCAGUUUGCCAGGCCCACCGGAGGUGCCCAGUAAAAUUUUGUCAAACAAAUACUGAUGAUGAAGUAUCCUGGGACUUGGCCCUGUCAGGGCAUAAUUGGAAUAUCAUUUGGAGAAAGUGUCAUGGAAGUUCUGCGUCCACAGCUUAUAAGAAUUGAUGGCCGGAAUUACAGGAAGAAUCCAGUCCAAGAACAGACCUAUCAACAUGAAGAAGAUGAAGAGGACUUCUAUCAAGGCUCCAUGGAGUGUGCUGAUGAGCCCUGUGAUGCCUACGAGGUGGAGCAGACCCCACAAGGAUUCCGGUCUACUUUGAGGGCCCCCAGCUUGCUCUAUAAGCAUAUAGUUGGAAAGAGAGGGGACACUAGGAAGAAAAUAGAAAUGGAGACCAAAACUUCUAUUAGCAUUCCUAAACCUGGACAAGACGGGGAAAUUGUAAUCACUGGCCAGCAUCGAAAUGGUGUAAUUUCAGCCCGAACACGGAUUGAUGUUCUUUUGGACACUUUUCGAAGAAAGCAGCCCUUCACUCACUUCCUUGCCUUUUUCCUCAAUGAAGUUGAGGUUCAGGAAGGAUUCCUGAGAUUCCAGGAGGAAGUACUGGCGAAGUGCUCCAUGGAUCAUGGGGUUGACAGCAGCAUUUUCCAGAAUCCUAAAAAGCUUCAUCUAACUAUUGGGAUGUUGGUGCUUUUGAGUGAGGAAGAGAUCCAGCAGACAUGUGAGAUGCUACAGCAGUGUAAAGAGGAAUUCAUUAAUGAUAUUUCUGGGGGUAAACCCCUAGAAGUGGAGAUGGCAGGGAUAGAAUACAUGAAUGAUGAUCCUGGCAUGGUGGAUGUUCUUUACGCCAAAGUCCAUAUGAAAGAUGGCUCCAACAGGCUACAAGAAUUAGUUGAUCGAGUGCUGGAACGUUUUCAGGCAUCUGGACUAAUAGUGAAAGAGUGGAAUAGUGUGAAACUGCAUGCUACAGUUAUGAAUACACUAUUCAGGAAAGACCCCAAUGCUGAAGGCAGGUACAAUCUCUACACAGCGGAAGGCAAAUAUAUCUUCAAGGAAAGAGAAUCAUUUGAUGGCCGAAAUAUUUUAAAGAGCUUUGCCUUGUUGCCCAGGCUGGAGUACAAUGAUGCAAUCUCCGCUCACUGCAACCUGUGCCUCCCGGGUUCAAGUGAUUCUCCUGCCUCAGCCUCCCAAGUAGCUGGGAUUACAGGUGUCUCUGAUGCAUAUUCUCAGAGCCUACCAGGAAAAUCCUAGAAUCGAGAAGGGCUUGGGACACAGAGAGCUAGUGGUUGUUUGAGAACUUCUACUUUGGCUCCCUAAAGCUGAAUUCAAUUCACAUCUCUCAGAGGUUCACCGUAGACAGCUUUGGAAACUACGCUUCCUGUGGACAAAUUGACUUCUCCUGAGGUGGAUCUUGGAAAGCACUAGAAACUAAACAUCUUCACCAGGUGCUGAAGAAAAGUGUCUUCGUUUUAAUUGCCAAGCAGGGAUGUGGACAUUUGGAUGGUGACUUUCCUGGGUGGUUCCCCAUAGAUUCACCAUUGCCUCUAAUGGUGUCUACACCCGUCAUACUACCAGCUGAGAUGGUGGUGGGCAUAAGGAGAAUUUGUGCCUAUAACCCUUAGUGUGUUCUGGUUUUUUUUCUUUUAAUUUUUAAAUUGUCGUAAAAUACUCAUAAAACAUACUGUCUUCACCAUUUUUAAGUGCACAGUUCAGUAACGUUAACUGUUAAUACAUUCAUAAUGCUGUGUGGCCGUCACCGCCGUCCAUCUCCAUAGGCUUCUCAGCUUGUAAAAUGGAAACUGUACCCAUUAAACAGUAAUUCCCACUCCUCCCAGCCCCCGCAGCCACCAUUCUGCUUUCUGUCUCUCUGGUUUUGACUAUUCUCAGUAUCUCAUAUAAGUGGAAUCAUACAGUGACUUGUCUUUUUGUGACUGGCUUAUUUCACUUAGCAUAAUGUCCUCAAGGUUCAUCCAUGUUGUGUCAGGUGACAGGAUUUCCUUCCUGUAUUAUACAUAUAAUGGAAUGUUCCGUUACAUGUGCGUACCACACUCUGUUCCUCCAUCAGUGAACACUUGGCUUGCUUCCUCUUGACUAUUGGGAGUAGUGCUAAUACAGACACGGGGGUGCAAAUAUCUCUUUGAGACUCUGCCUUUAAUUCCUUUACCACCCAGAGUUUUAUCUUUAGCAAAAUAACCAUUAAAGUUGUUUGCCUUUUACUUUGCUUGGUCUAUCAUUUUCCUACCAAAGUUUGUCCUCUUAAUAUUUGUUGGAUUCCUGUUCCUUCACCCCAUCCCCACCCUCAUCUUCCCAUGCCCCUGAUGGAGUUGCAGUGUUGCAGCCCUUUUUUGUUUACUUUUCAAGGCAGCAGCAAAAGAAACUGAUGAUAUCAGCAGGACUGUGCAGAGUUCCCUGGAAGAAUGUCAGCCACAGGAGGCCCUCACUCCUCCCUCACCACGGACCAGCAGAGGGAGGCGGGAAUGCUGGGGAGCCCCAGCCUCCCACCCCUGCCUCCUCACAUUCUUCCUCCCUCCAUGUCCUCUCCUUCUUCUCCUUCCUUAUUCUUGCCUUGAUUCUUUCUCUCUUUAUAUUCUUUAACUGCACUUCUGAACUCUGUGUUAAGUUGCUACAUUGUGAGGACUGUGUCUAACAGUGAGAUUUAUUAUUGGGACUGCACAAAUCACUUGUGAAUAAAAUGUUUAACGGUG